GAGUCGGUGUGUUGUGGACUCGUGGUGCUGGCUGCCGCUGUUCAGGCGGCCGGGAACGGGCGGUGGGGAGCGGGCGGAGCUGGCCCUGCCUCUGCCUGGCCGGCGCCGCAGUCGGCGCGGGCCGCGCCCGCCGCCGCCAACUGCCCUGAGCGCUUGCUGAGGCCGAGGGAGACGUCGGGGCCUGCACCUGGAGGGAGCCUGCCGCGCUGGCCCCGAGGAGGGGGCGUUGCCAUGGCGACAGCCUCUCCCGCUGCUGACGGGGGGCGGGGGCGGCCCUGGGAAGGAGGGCUGGUCUCCUGGCCCCCCGCCCCUCCCCUUACUCUCCCCUGGACUUGGAUGGGCCCGAGUUGGGGGCAACACCCCGGGGUGGGUGAUGCUGAAUGGCCCCGCCAAGAUUGGGCCCUGGUUAAUGCAUGCGGGGUGAGGGUCGCGGUGCGCAGAAUUUAUGCAACCUGGGGUGCUGGCCCAUGUGCUUACCCUGGAUGCUUACUUAAUCUACUGAGUAAUGUUCUGGCGGAGGGGGAGCGGGGCAGAGCUUUGCAAGACAGGAUGGCAUUGGGGCUUUCCAGCUCUCACAGAACCUUCAGCAUCCCCAGCUGCCGGUCUUGGCAUCUUCGAAGUAAGGAGAGUUUUAGAUGCUUCUGGAUGUUCAAUGCUAGCACCUUUACAGACUGGAGCAGCUCGAUUUUCUUCGUAUUUACUUUCAAGAGCAAGAAAAGUGCUGGGCUCCCACUUAUUUUCUCCCUGUGGUGUUCCGGAGUUCUGCUCCAUAUCCACCAGAAAGCUGGCGGCCCACGGCUUUGGCGCAUCCAUGGCGGCAAUGGUGUCCUUCCCUCCCCAGAGGUAUCACUACUUUUUAGUGCUGGACUUUGAGGCCACGUGCGACAAGCCACAGAUUCAUCCUCAGGAAAUCAUCGAGUUCCCCAUCCUAAAGCUAAAUGGCCGGACCAUGGAGAUUGAGUCUACCUUUCACAUGUAUGUCCAGCCUGUAGUCCAUCCACAGCUUACCCCAUUCUGUACAGAGCUCACCGGGAUUAUUCAAGCCAUGGUGGAUGGUCAGCCAAGCCUGCAGCAAGUGCUGGAGAGGGUCGAUGAAUGGAUGGCGAAGGAAGGCCUCUUAGAUCCAAACGUCAAGUCAAUUUUUGUCACCUGUGGAGACUGGGACUUAAAAGUCAUGCUCCCAGGCCAGUGCCAGUACUUGGGCUUGCCAGUGGCGGAUUACUUCAAGCAGUGGAUUAAUCUGAAAAAGGCUUACAGCUUCGCCAUGGGCUGCUGGCCCAAGAAUGGACUUCUAGACAUGAACAAGGGCCUCAGCCUGCAACACAUAGGCCGGCCCCACAGCGGCAUUGACGACUGCAAGAACAUUGCCAACAUCAUGAAGACACUCGCCUAUCGAGGCUUCAUCUUCAAGCAGACAUCGAAGCCGUUCUGAUUGGCCGAGGACAGGAUGGGGCAGGACAGGGUAGCUGUUUGGCCCAGCCCAGAAUCCUCCUCUCCCUCACCAGAGGGGAAGAGGGAGAGUGGCAUAGCUCUGUGUCCAGAGUGUCCCCAGCUGCCCUGUGGGCUCAUGCCCUUGGCGUGGGCUUGUGCCCUUGCAAGGGCUUGGCCACUUGGCCCUUCUGGAGCAGACACUUUGUGCCCCCCAUCCCCACCCCUCAAUCUCAGCCCAGUAUCAGCCCCUCCCAUUGCGGGCCUGGGCUAGGGGGACCCAGGCACUCACCGCCUCCUCCCUGGUACACAGGCUUCUGUGGGGCCACCAAGCCCCUCCUGUGCCCCCUCCCAUCCAUAGUGCAUGGUGUGUGGUGCCCCCAGGGCUCCAGGACAGAUCAGGCCCCACCUUGUGUCUACCCCCAUCCCCGCUGUGAACGUGCCACUGAAUAAAGUCGGGGAAACGAGGCACUGGGUGUGUGUGCAAAGCCA